AGUGCUCCAGAGAAAGGCCGUCCUGCAGCACCCGCCGCUGUCGCCGACCGCCCGCACAUCCGUCGGGUGAGUCCCGCGUGCCCCCGCGGCCGCGGGGCCUAGUGCGCGCGCAGUAACCUGUUUGUGGCCUGGUCGGCGUCCCGUAGGGCGCCCUCCCGCGCUAGGCCGGCCGGCGUGGCGCUCGGCGCCGAACAGGCCCCGAGGAGGCCGCAGUUAGGCCUAGUGAUUAUCCAGUUGCCCUGAGCGGCUGCGGAGGUGCGCUCCAUAAGCGGGCAGGGUGGGAAAAGUUCGCCCGUUUGUCCGGAAGGCAGUUGAUGGACCUGGGGUCGACACCACUGCGGACGCAGGGCACGGCACGGGGGCGAGAAGGCGAAGGCUGCAGGCGUGAGGAGCUGUGACUAAUGAGAAUUAAAGGCCAUGGAUGAAGAUGAAUUUGAAUUGCAGCCACAAGAGCCAAACUCAUUUUUUGAUGGAAUAGGAGCUGAUGCUACACACAUGGAUGGUGAUCAGAUUGUUGUGGAAAUACAAGAAGCAGUUUUUGUUUCUAAUAUUGUGGAUUCUGACAUAACUGUGCAUAACUUUGUUCCUGAUGACCCAGACUCAGUUGUAAUCCAAGAUGUUGUUGAAGAUGUUGUCAUAGAGGAGGAUGUUCAGUGCUCAGAUAUCUUAGAAGAGGCAGAUGUAUCUGAAAAUGUCAUCAUUCCUGAGCAAGUGCUGGACUCAGAUGUAACUGAAGAAGUUUCUUUACCACACUGCACAGUCCCAGAUGAUGUUUUAGCUUCUGACAUUACUUCAACCUCAAUGUCUAUGCCAGAACAUGUUUUAACGAGUGAAUCCAUGCAUGUGUGUGACAUUGGACAUGUUGAACAUAUGGUGCAUGAUAGUGUAGUGGAAGCAGAAAUCAUUACUGAUCCUCUGACGAGUGACAUAGUUUCAGAAGAAGUAUUGGUAGCAGACUGUGCCCCUGAAGCAGUCAUAGAUGCCAGCGGGAUCUCAGUGGACCAGCAAGAUAAUGACAAAGCCAGCUGUGAGGACUACCUAAUGAUUUCGUUGGAUGAUGCUGGCAAAAUAGAACAUGAUGGUUCCACUGGAGUGACCAUCGAUGCAGAAUCAGAAAUGGAUCCUUGUAAAGUGGAUAGCACUUGUCCUGAAGUCAUCAAGGUGUACAUUUUUAAAGCUGACCCUGGAGAAGAUGACUUAGGUGGAACUGUAGACAUUGUGGAGAGUGAACCUGAAAAUGAUCAUGGAGUUGAACUACUUGAUCAGAACAGCAGUAUUCGUGUUCCCAGGGAAAAGAUGGUUUAUAUGACUGUCAAUGACUCUCAACAAGAAGAUGAAGAUUUAAAUGUUGCUGAAAUUGCUGAUGAAGUUUAUAUGGAAGUGAUCGUAGGAGAGGAGGAUGCUGCUGUUGCAGCAGCAGCAGCUGCUGUGCAUGAGCAGCAAAUUGAUGAGGAUGAAAUGAAAACCUUCGUACCAAUUGCAUGGGCAGCAGCUUAUGGUAAUAAUUCUGAUGGAAUUGAAAACCGGAAUGGCACUGCAAGUGCCCUCUUGCACAUAGAUGAGUCUGCUGGCCUUGGCAGACUGGCUAAACAGAAACCAAAGAAAAAGAGAAGACCUGAUUCCAGGCAGUACCAAACAGCAAUAAUUAUUGGCCCUGAUGGUCAUCCUUUGACUGUCUAUCCUUGCAUGAUUUGUGGGAAGAAGUUUAAGUCGAGGGGUUUUUUGAAAAGACACAUGAAAAACCAUCCUGAACACCUUGCCAAGAAGAAGUACCACUGUACUGACUGUGAUUACACUACCAAUAAGAAGAUAAGUUUACAUAACCACCUGGAGAGCCACAAGCUGACCAGCAAGGCAGAGAAGGCCAUUGAAUGUGAUGAGUGUGGGAAGCAUUUUUCUCAUGCAGGGGCUUUGUUUACUCACAAAAUGGUGCAUAAGGAAAAAGGGGCCAACAAAAUGCACAAGUGUAAAUUCUGUGAAUAUGAGACAGCUGAACAGGGGUUAUUGAAUCGCCACCUCUUGGCAGUCCACAGCAAGAACUUUCCUCAUAUUUGUGUGGAGUGUGGUAAAGGUUUCCGACACCCGUCGGAACUGAGAAAGCACAUGCGAAUCCAUACCGGCGAGAAGCCAUACCAAUGCCAGUACUGUGAAUAUAGGUCUGCAGACUCUUCUAACUUGAAAACACAUAUAAAAACAAAGCAUAGUAAAGAGAUGCCAUUCAAGUGUGACAUUUGUCUUCUGACUUUCUCAGAUACCAAAGAAGUGCAGCAACAUACUCUUGUCCACCAAGAAAGCAAAACACAUCAGUGUUUGCAUUGCGACCACAAGAGUUCAAACUCAAGUGAUUUGAAACGACAUGUAAUUUCAGUUCAUACGAAAGACUAUCCUCAUAAGUGUGAGAUGUGCGAGAAAGGCUUUCACAGGCCUUCAGAACUUAAGAAACAUGUGGCUGUCCACAAAGGUAAAAAAAUGCACCAAUGUAGACAUUGUGACUUUAAGAUUGCAGACCCAUUUGUUCUAAGUCGCCAUAUUCUCUCAGUUCACACAAAGGAUCUUCCAUUUAGGUGUAAGAGAUGUAGAAAGGGAUUUAGGCAACAAAAUGAGCUUAAAAAGCAUAUGAAGACACACAGUGGCAGGAAAGUAUAUCAGUGUGAGUACUGUGAGUAUAGCACUACAGAUGCCUCAGGCUUUAAACGGCACGUUAUUUCCAUUCAUACAAAAGACUAUCCUCAUCGGUGUGAGUACUGCAAGAAAGGCUUCCGAAGACCUUCAGAAAAGAACCAGCACAUAAUGAGACACCAUAAAGAAGUUGGUCUGCCCUAACAGUGUGUCUACAAGCUUGUAAAGAUGUUGGCCUUGAAGCAGAAAAUUCAUUUUUUAAAGCCAGUCUUGUUCACAUCCAUUACUAUACAUUGAAUUAUGCUGUGUAAAAAUAGAAUUAUUGCUUCUAGUCCACUUUUCUUUACAUUUUAUUCAAUACGCUGUCCUGAAUCCUAUUCAGUUUCUUUAAUAGAUGAGGAAAAAUAGCAACAAGCAAGUUGCUUAUAAUAAAAUAAUUUGUGAUUCUAUACUGAAUUUUCAGUCAUAAAAGCUUUACUAUUUAUUUACAUAUUUAUUCAUGUUCAUGGUACUCUUCUAAGACAAAAUCAGAUUGAUAACUAUGAAAGUAACAUUUUUGACCCAUUUCCUCCUACACAAGUGUUUCACAUUGGAGACAUCUGCUAAUAUAAAUGGGAGGUUUUACUGUCAAGUCCAAUUAGCAAAACGUGGUAAUAAUUUUUUUGUCAGUAUUUUCAGAUUACAUGAUAAAAUUUUACAUUUGAGCUUCUAGCAUUGAUUAAUAUAGGAUAUUGACCACGUUUAUGUUUAAAUUUCAUUUUGUUCAGCAGACAAAAUGUACUUCCCUUAACUUUCAUUAAUAGUGUUUACAUCUUUUGUCAGCACAGCAAACUUUUAGAAAGUAAUAGUUUUACUUAUUUUUAUCUUCUGUUUUCUCUUUGUACUGCUUUGUCUUGCAUUGUGUUCCAACACAUGAGACUUACUGCUCACUGAAUUUUGGAGUCUUUUAGAGGUAAAUUGUGGACUCAGGAUUUUUUGAAACUUGGUGUGUAACUCUAAAUCUUGUAUAUGCAUCUUUGUUGCUUAUUACAUAUUUACACACACAACCACAAAUUUUAAACUUAUGAUGAAAAUUUACAAUAACCUGAAAGAUCCAGAGAUGUAUGAGAGCAUUUUGUAACUUGUUAUUCAGUUACUAAAUUUGAGGUGAAUAAUUAAAAAGAAAAGGACAUUAGGAGAGUGAAAAUCUUCUCUUCAAAUAAUCUUUGAUAGAUAAAAAUGGAAGGUAAGAUGUUUCUAGAUAGAAUGUUUUCAUACAAUUUCAGCUUCAUAUCAUAAAUUUUUCUGGAAAGCUAUUUCAGACAUAGAUUUCAUAGUAUUUUUCUGAGAAUCCUGUGAAGGAACGCUGUCUCUUUGCAAAGUAAGGAGGACUAAGGGAAAAUGAUGGUACCAUGUAACAGAAUGAGAGCUAAUUCCAAAUUAGCAACUUCAUCCUGCUUUCUAUUUUACAUUGAGUAAAGUUUUAAAAAGACAACAGUCAAGUUGAUUUUGAUUAGAAGAUAAAAGUACAUAAUGAAAAUCCAUGGCCUUAUUUGGAAUAUAUAUCACUUUCCAAAUUUUAUUAUUUAUUUGAGAGUUAAUAAGUUAAUGUUAUUAAGCAGUUAAUAAUUUAUAUGUAUGGAUAUAAUAUAAAAUGAAUUCAUAUAAUUAAAAAGAAUUUGGUUAAUAAGAAUUUGGAGAAUGGAAAAUACAUUUUUAGGUUCCUUAAUUUGGCUGUUGGUACCUGUGUAUUUGGAAUAUUUUAGGGGAUUCGAAUUUUUUUUAACCCACAUUACAGCUACCUUCUAGCUUUAGUAUGGUAGUGCUUCAUUCAACUUUUGCUGUCAGGUUUUUAUUUUCACCUUUUUCUGUGCCACCAAUUCAAAAGUUAUAGGAUUAGGAAAUAUAAAUUUAUAUUUGGUGAUUGGCAGCCUCUGAAAUGUUAGAUUAAUUUGAUCUAGUUCUAAAGUGCUUUAGUCAUAUAUGAAUUUAAACCUAGUACCAUCCAAAACCAUGUAAUGGAUUUUAAGAAUCUGUUAGGCCUUCUUAGCCUUUAUACAUGUCCCUACCUGAUUUUUACUGUCCUUCAUGAUCCUGUUCUUGAAAACUUCAGUUUGUAUUUGAGAAUCCUUUAAAUCUCCUUCCAAUUUGUUUUCUCCCUGAAGUAAUAUAAAAGGAAGUAUUUAAGUGAAAGUUUAAGAGUUUUAAAACAUUCUUUAAAAUUAAUACAGAUAGUUAGCUAUUUAUCUUUUAAAAAUAAACUAAGGUAAAAAACGUGACACUUUACAUAUUUCAUAUUUUUCAUAUAGUCUGGAGGUAUACACAGUUGUUUUGUUUUUAACCACGGUAUUGAAACCUUUAAAAGGUAAUUAAGCAUUUGGUCAAGUAAAUAUAGAACAUUUGUAUAAAGAAAGAAAUGAAAUUGUGCUUAAUGUUAUAUACUGUUAUUAUUUGCAGGCUGGUUUUAAUUCUUAAUUUGAUUAGCAAAGCUAAAAAAGUGGAUGUUGAAGUUGAAAGUUUUAAAGAGGUACAAAAUCUUACAAGGACAUAAAUUAUUAUUUGGUUGAAAAAUAGCCUAUUAGAUAUUGUAUGUCCCUUCCUCUGUACAAAUUGUAAAAUACUUAAAAUAACUAUGAAGAAUUCAUAUAGGAAGUGUGAUACUAUUGUAAAUGUGUAUUUGAGAAUAUGCAAAAAUAAAAAUAAUAUUUUACUGUUAAUAAAUGUUUACUUGUAUAUGA